GAUACCCGGGACUGGGCUGCGGCGGUUAGUCCUCUCCCGGCCGCCGUCGCCUCCGACAUAUUGCCCGCAGGAGCUGCGGCGGCGAAGCGGAGAGCACCGGGGGGAGGAGAUGGGAGGACGAAGAGGUCCCAACAGGACAUCUUACUGUCGAAAUCCGCUCUGUGAGCCGGGAUCCUCGGGGGGCUCUAGUGGAAGCCACACUUCCAGUGCAUCGGUGACCAGUGUUCGUUCCCGCACCAGGAGCAGUUCUGGAACAGGCCUCUCCAGCCCUCCUCUGGCCACCCAAACUGUUGUGCCUCUACAGCACUGCAAGAUCCCCGAGCUGCCAGUCCAGGCCAGCAUUCUGUUUGAGUUGCAGCUCUUCUUCUGCCAGCUCAUAGCACUCUUCGUCCACUACAUCAACAUCUACAAGACAGUGUGGUGGUAUCCACCUUCCCACCCACCCUCCCACACCUCCCUGAACUUCCAUCUGAUCGACUUCAACUUGCUGAUGGUGACCACCAUCGUUCUGGGCCGCCGCUUCAUUGGGUCCAUCGUGAAGGAGGCCUCUCAGAGGGGGAAGGUCUCCCUCUUUCGCUCCAUCCUGCUGUUCCUCACUCGCUUCACCGUUCUCACGGCAACAGGCUGGAGUCUGUGCCGAUCCCUCAUCCACCUCUUCAGGACCUACUCCUUCCUGAACCUCCUGUUCCUCUGCUAUCCGUUUGGGAUGUACAUUCCGUUCCUGCAGCUGAAUUGCGACCUCCGCAAGACAAGCCUCUUCAACCACAUGGCCUCCAUGGGGCCCCGGGAGGCGGUCAGUGGCCUGGCAAAGAGCCGGGACUACCUCCUGACACUGCGGGAGACGUGGAAGCAGCACACAAGACAGCUGUAUGGCCCGGACGCCAUGCCCACCCAUGCCUGCUGCCUGUCACCCAGCCUCAUCCGCAGUGAGGUGGAGUUCCUCAAGAUGGACUUCAACUGGCGCAUGAAGGAAGUGCUCGUCAGCUCCAUGCUGAGCGCCUACUAUGUGGCCUUUGUGCCUGUCUGGUUCGUGAAGAACACACAUUACUAUGACAAGCGCUGGUCCUGUGAACUCUUCCUGCUGGUGUCCAUCAGCACCUCCGUGAUCCUCAUGCAGCACCUGCUGCCUGCCAGCUACUGUGACCUGCUGCACAAGGCCGCCGCCCAUCUGGGCUGUUGGCAGAAGGUGGACCCAGCGCUGUGCUCCAACGUGCUGCAGCACCCGUGGACUGAAGAAUGCAUGUGGCCGCAGGGCGUGCUGGUGAAGCACAGCAAGAACGUCUACAAAGCCGUAGGCCACUACAACGUGGCUAUCCCCUCUGACGUCUCCCACUUCCGCUUCCAUCUCGGCCGGGCAUGGUGGCUCACGCCUGUAAUCCCAGCACUUUGGGAGACCAAGGCAGACAGAUCACCUGAGGUCAGGAGUUCAAGACCAGACCAGCCUGGUCAACAUGGUGAAACCUCGUCUCCACUAAAAAUACAAAAAUUAGCCAGGUAUGGUGGCGGGCGCCUGUAAUCCCAGCUACUCGGGAGGCUGAGGAGGGAGAACCACUUGAACUCAGGAGACGGAGGUUGCAGUGAGCCGAGAUCAUGCCACUGCACUCCAGCCUGGGCAACAGAGCAAGACUCAUUCUCAAAAAUAAAUAAAUAAAUAACUGCAGCUCAUUUGGUUGUAGAUCUUUGAGAACAUUGGACAGAGGGAGAGAAGAUGAUACAGUAAAAGAAGGGGCUCUUGGCAGUGAAAGACAAUACUGUCUUCAUUUGUUACUGUGUGCCAGGCAUGUCGUUAAGCACUCUCCAUGUACCUUCCUACUCAGCCUUACCCUGAACCUUGUACGUGAAAGAUAUGCUAGGGUUAUCUCUGUUUUUAGAUACUGAAAUCAGCUAAGAGAGUUUAACUUGUUAAAGGGUGCCUUCUUGGGAAACUUGAGAACCUAAUGGUAAUGACUCAUGACUUAGCUAUGGAAAGGGCUGCUCAAAAUUAUCUAAACUAGUGAUCUCUAUUUUUUUUUAAAUUUCACUAUGAAAUCCCCUCCCCCCCUUUUUUAAAAAAAACAAUCAGAGGCCAAAAUCCAAUAUAUGGGACAUCCUGGCACUGCUCUGUUUGGAGGAGUUAGAACCCCCUUCACUUCCUGCUCACCCCCGCUGUAACUCCUAAAGGAUCCCCUUGAAACCUGGGGCUCUAAGGAACACAGCAUGAGAAAUCACUGACCUAGACUGAUGUCUUCAUUUCACAGUUGAGACAUCCAAGCCCCAGAGAGGAAAGGGACUUGACCAAAGUAUUGCAGCCUGUUAGGUGCAGAGCUGAGCCUGAUAUCCUGGUCUCUUGGCCUCCCAUUUCCUACCACUUCUCCUGUCCUGUAAGCAGCUCUUGAGAUUUAGGUACCUUGGCCCCUGUGGAAUCAAAAUCCCUAGACACUGUGCACUCUUUUGAACUCAUCAGAGAUUUUUUUUUAGUCCCUACGUUCUACCUUGCUGUUGAGAGUGAGCUGUUGCCAUGUCCCUUGGCAGCUUCCAGCCUAGCUAGGGAUGUACCUAUGAAGUAGUAGGUAAUUCAGGCUGUAGAGUCUGUAAUAACUUUCCAUGCCUAUGUCAUAGGAUUCUAAUUUGUUCAGGCCCAGCAAUACCCAGGAGAUGACAUUAAAAGGUGUUGAUUUUAUUGAGGGUCAGUGGAUGAGGGAGAAAAAGUUUUCAAAAAUUAAAAAAAAUUUUUUUAAAGGUGUUGACUUUAGACCACAAAAAGAGUUUGAGAGAGCAAGCAGAACCUGUCAAGAAAGACUUCCUAGGGGAGGUAGAAGUUGAACAGGAUCUUAGAUGACUUACAUCAGAAGCAGCAGUCCUAUCAGGAGGAAUACCACAAGCAAAGGCAGAUGAGGUGGCAAAGUCCACAUCCAACCCCAGAAAGUCUUCUUCCCCACCCAUGUCUGCAUGGGGCCCCAGGAGGCUGUCCCCUUCACUGGCCCACCCAGAACCCCCAUCCAGGAGGAAGAUUUCUGGAGCACACCUUUUAGCCAUGCCCACCCGCUUCCGGGCAGUUCUUUUUCAGCAAACCCCUGCGGAUCCUCAACAUCCUCCUGCUGCUGGAGGGCGCUGUCAUUGUCUAUCAGCUGUACUCCCUAAUGUCCUCUGAAAAGUGGCACCAGACCAUCUCGCUGGCCCUCAUCCUCUUCAGCAACUACUAUGCCUUCUUCAAGCUGCUCCGGGACCGCUUGGUAUUGGGCAAGGCCUACUCAUACUCUGCUAGCCCCCAGAGAGACCUGGACCACCGUUUCUCCUGAGCCCUGGGGUCACCUCAGGGACAGCGUCCAGGCUUCAGCCAAGGGCUCCCUGGCAAGGGGCUGUUGGGUAGAAGUGGUGGUGGGGGGGACAAAAGACAAAAAAAUCCACCAGAGCUUUGUAUUUUUGUUACGUACUGUUUCUUUGAUAAUUGAUGUGAUAAGGAAAAAAGUCCUAUUUUUAUACUCCCAA